GGGAGAAGCGUUUCCGGUGGCGGCGGAGGCUGCACUGAGCGGGACCUGCGAGCAGCGCGGGCGGCAGCCCGGGGGAAGCGGUGAGUCGCGGGCGGCAGGCCCAGCCAGUCCGGGACCAUGUCUGGAGAACUACCACCAAACAUUAACAUCAAGGAACCUCGAUGGGAUCAAAGCACUUUCAUUGGACGAGCCAAUCAUUUCUUCACUGUAACUGACCCCAGGAACAUUCUGUUAACCAACGAACAACUCGAGAGUGCGAGAAAAAUAGUACAUGAUUACAGGCAAGGAAUUGUUCCUCCUGGUCUUACAGAAAAUGAAUUGUGGAGAGCAAAGUACAUCUAUGAUUCAGCUUUUCAUCCUGACACUGGUGAGAAGAUGAUUUUGAUAGGAAGAAUGUCAGCCCAGGUUCCCAUGAACAUGACCAUCACAGGUUGUAUGAUGACGUUUUACAGGACUACGCCGGCUGUGCUGUUCUGGCAGUGGAUUAACCAGUCCUUCAAUGCCGUCGUCAAUUACACCAACAGAAGUGGAGACGCACCCCUCACUGUCAAUGAGUUGGGAACAGCUUACGUUUCUGCAACAACUGGUGCCGUAGCAACAGCUCUAGGACUCAAUGCAUUGACCAAGCAUGUCUCACCACUGAUAGGACGUUUUGUUCCCUUUGCUGCCGUAGCUGCUGCUAAUUGCAUUAAUAUUCCAUUAAUGAGGCAAAGGGAACUCAAAGUUGGCAUUCCCGUCACGGAUGAGAAUGGGAACCGCUUGGGGGAGUCGGCGAACGCUGCGAAACAAGCCAUCACGCAAGUUGUCGUGUCCAGGAUUCUCAUGGCAGCCCCUGGCAUGGCCAUCCCUCCAUUCAUUAUGAACACUUUGGAAAAGAAAGCCUUUUUGAAGAGGUUCCCAUGGAUGAGUGCACCCAUUCAAGUUGGGUUAGUUGGCUUCUGUUUGGUGUUUGCUACACCCCUGUGUUGUGCCCUGUUUCCUCAGAAAAGUUCCAUGUCUGUGACAAGCUUGGAGGCCGAGUUGCAAGCUAAGAUCCAAGAGAGCCAUCCUGAAUUGCGACGCGUGUACUUCAAUAAGGGAUUGUAAAGCAGGGAGGAAACCUCUGCAGCUCAUUCUGCCACUGCAAAGCUGGUGUAGCCAUGCUGGUGAGAAAAAUCCUGUUCAACCUGGGUUCUCCCAGUUACGGAAACCUUUUAAAGAUCCACAUUAGCCUUUUAGAAUAAAGCUGCUACUUUAACAGAGCACCUGGCGUGGGCCAAGUGCCUGAUACUCCCUUACACUGAAUCAUGUUAUGAUUUAUAGAAAUACCUUUCCUGUAGCUUUUAUAGUCAUUGUUUUUCAAAGACGAUAUACCAGCCCUCACCCAGGUUUUAAAAAAGCACUGGUAGGCAUAGAAUAGGUGCUCAGUAUAUGGUCAGUAAAUGUUCUAUUGAUUAUCAAUCAGUGAAAAAAGAAAUCUGUUUAAAAUACUGAAUUUUCAUCUCACUCCCAUUGCAAAUCAAGGAGAUCUCAGCAGUGAACUGGGAAAAUACAAAAGCUCUGGGCUAAUCUAUAAAAACUUACCCUGAAAUAUUAAGGGCAGUUUGCUUCUAGUUUGGGGAUUGCGCUAGCCCAAUGAAGGUGAUGAAGCUUUUGGAUUUGGAGGGUAAAAGCUCCUUCACACCCCUUCCAAAAGUCAGUCACAGACCACUGCAACAUGCCUUCCCUGCUGGAUCAUUAUAUACAUUCAGAUUGUGAGUGGAUUGCCUUGGUUGACUUUUAAUUUAUUGUUUUUUGUUCUUAUAAAGAUGAUAAUCUUACCUUGCAGUUAUUGACUUUAUAUUCAAUUAUUUACAUCAAAUAAUGAAAUAACUGAAAUGUACAAAUGUCAAAUUUUGGAAGUAUAUUCAAUACCAAUGCUGUAUGAGUGGGCUGAAUCCAGUUCAUUGUUUUUUUUUUGGUAAGAAGUGAGACUACAGUUCCAGCUACCUACAUGUCUUUUCUUGUCAUCCUUAUAGAUCUCUUUGGCUUUCAGAAAGAUACAGUGAUAAUGUGUGUAUGAAUCAGUCACAAUGAAUUUUACUUGAAUAUUGUAUGUUGCAUUCCACUUCAUUUGAAAAUAAUGAAACCAUGUACCACUGUUUACAUCAUCUGUAGUGAUUUCAUAGAUAAUAUAUUUAAUAUGACAGAUUAUGUUUCAACUCUGUAGAUGUUUAACGUCAUAGACAGUUGGCCCUCUGUAUCCGUGAGCUCUAUAUCUGUGAAUUCAACCAAGUUUGGAUGGAAAAUUUUUUUUUUUUUUUUUUUUUUGAGACGGAGUCUCGCUCUGUCACCCAGGCUGGAGUGCAGUGGCGUAGUCUCGGCUCACUGCAAGCUCCGCCUCCCGGGUUCACGCCGUUCUCCUGCCUCAGCCUCUCUGAGAAGCUGGGACUACAGGCGCCCGCCACCACGCCCGGCUAAUUUUUUUGUAUUUUUAGUAGAGACGGGGUUUCACUGUGGUCUCGAUCUCCUGACCUCGUGAUCCGCCCGCCUUGGCCUCCCAAGGUGCUGGGAUUACAAGCGUGAGCCACCGCACCCGGCCUGAAAAUAUUUUCUAAAAAGAUAAAAAAUAUACAUAACGAUGAAAAAUAAUACAAAUUUAAAAACCAAUACAGUAUAACAACUAUUUACAUAGUGCUUACAUUGUAUUAGGUGUUAUAAGCAAUCUAGAGAUGAUUUAGCAAGUAUACAGGAGGAUGUGCCUAGGUUAUAUGCAAAUACUGUGCCAUUUUAUAUCAGGAACUUGAGCAUCUGCAGAUAUUGGUAUCGGAGGGCGGUCCUGGAACCAAGCAUCCACGGAUACUGAGGGGUGACAUUUCAUGAAGUGUAGAUCAUUGUAUUCAGAGAUUGUAAAUGAAAAAAAUAUAGAAACUAUUUAGUUUUGGUAGAUUUUUUUUCUGACAAUGUGACCAGACUGAAUUUCCUCAUAAAGAAAAAAUGGCGUGCCUUGUGUCUGUGUUUCUCUUUUCUCUGAAAGGAUUAAUAGAUCUGAAGCUUUGGGCCACUCAGAGCCUUCCUUGAUGCUGCCAGAGUCUUCUUAUUUAGAUUUUCUGUCUUAAACCAUUGGAAGCAAAACGGUUUUCCCAUGACAUUCUGGCCUUGGACAGAUUCUGUUGUCCUCGACGCGUCUCUUUAUAAAGUGGUAAAAGCCUGAAAUUCAGGGCAGCUCUCCAUGAGGUGCUGAAGGGCUCUUUUCAUAAGAAGCUAAGGCACUGCUGCCUGCCCCAGGUGUCCCGCUCCUCUCAGAGUCCUCCCCCUACCAGGUAGUGUGUAGCUCCAUUUCAGAAUGUUAACCUCCAGUGAAGAGCUAAUGACUGGUUAGAAGAUUGACAAACUAACCAAAAUUUUACACACUCCGGUUAUGUGUGUGAAAGGUUAUAAAAGGAAUGGCCGGGUGCGGUGGCUCACCCCUGUAAUCCCAGCACUUUGGGAGGCCGAGGCGGGUGGAUCACCUGAGGUCAGGAGUUUGAGACCAGCCUGGCCAACAUGGAGAAACCCCGCCUCUACUAAAAAUACAAAAAAUUAGCCAGGCAUGGAGGCACAUGCCUAUAAUCCCAGCUACUCGGGAGGCUGAGGUAGGAGAAUCGCUUGAAUCCGGGAGCUGGAGGUUGCAGUGAGCCAAGAUCGCACCAUUGCACUCCAGCCUGGGCAACAAGAGCGAAACUCCAUCUCAAAAAAAAAAAAAAGAGAUUAUAAAAGGGAUGAUGAACAUGGAGCUGCAUCUUUUUAAACGUUGUUUUUUGAUGCUUCAGACUCUUAAUGCUUUUAUAUAAAGCUAUCAACUGUAUGUUGAUCACAGUUUAUAAGAAAGAACAAAUCAAGAUUGGCAAUCCUUGCCGAUCUUUUAGAAAUACCUUUUCUGGAGAAAAAAAAAUCCACAUGAAGUGCAAUAAGCUUAUAAAGCUAAGUAGUUAUUAAUAUUUCUAUUAACAUGAUACAAAGGAUGAUGAUUGUAAGUGUUUACUGACUGGCAGCUUUUAUUUCAGUAUUAGCACAGCGUCUUGCCAGUGUUGGAGGCCAUGUAUUAUUUCAGUUCAACUGGAUGAAAUGUUAAAUAAACUCAGAAUGAAAAUAAA